AUGCGCGCGCGUCUCCUGUCGCCGGCCGCUGCGCUCCGCGGCGCGGAAUAGAAUGAACUGUAACAAAACAAGCCGAGCCUUUGUAUCUGCUUAAAGGGGCCGCGAGCACUUACCUCCCGCCCUGCUCCCCGCCGCCCCGCCACCGCGUCUUCAGGGCUCCCGGCAACUGGCUGGAAGGGCUUCCCUCACCCUCAGUAACAGCCUGCCAGCGAGGAGAGGCGAGCCGGGCGGGAGGCAAAGAGGAGGCACCGCAUUUGUAAAAGGCAAGAGAGAAAGGAAGGAAGGAAAAAAAAAUAACCCGAGCGGCGCAGAGUGGACUCUGGUCCGGGAGAGCACGGGCGGGCGCCGGAACGUGGACCCAGAGGCACCGGAAUGCAAACAAAGCUCGCGGGCGCCUGUGCGGGGCUCGCGGGGAAGCCCAGAAAGUUUGUUUUAUGAUGGCUUGAGUGCGCGAGCGUGUGCAGGGGAGCGAGGCUGCCAAGUUUCUCUCUCCUGUUUUGUGAUUUGGGGAGAGAUGUUUCUCCCAUGAACAAGCGGAGGCUUGGGGGCUCGUGCUGUGGGGGGCACCUGUCUCUCGUUUUAUUUUUUUGGAGGAGGGGUGUAACUCAUCAUGUCCAAAGUGAUCCAGAAGAAGAACCACUGGACUAGCAGGGUUCACGAAUGCACCGUGAAGCGGGGACCCCAGGGCGAGCUGGGGGUGACGGUGCUGGGAGGCGCGGAGCACGGGGAGUUUCCGUACGUCGGAGCGGUGGCGGCGGUCGAGGCAGCGGGGCUUCCCGGCGGCGGCGAGGGCCCGAGGCUGGGCGAAGGGGAGCUGCUUCUGGAGGUGCAGGGGGUCCGGGUGUCCGGCUUGCCCCGCUAUGACGUGCUGGGGGUCAUCGACAGCUGCAAGGAGGCCGUCACCUUCAAGGCCGUCAGACAAGGAAGGCAG